GUUCCCGGAAGUAGAAGACAGCGGCGUUGCCAUGGCGGCGUCUCUGGGGCAGGUGUUGGCUCUGGUGCUGGUGGCCGCUCUGUGGGGUGGCACGCAGCCGCUGCUGAAGCGGGCCUCCGCCGGCCUGCAGCGGGUUCAUGAGCCGACCUGGGCCCAGCAGUUGCUACAGGAGAUGAAGACCCUCUUCUUGAAUACUGAGUACCUGAUGCCCUUUCUCCUCAACCAGUGUGGAUCCCUUCUCUAUUACCUCACCUUGGCAUCGACAGAUCUGACCCUGGCUGUGCCCAUCUGUAACUCUCUGGCUAUCAUCUUCACACUGAUUGUUGGGAAGGCCCUUGGAGAAGAUAUUGGUGGAAAACGAGCAGUUGCUGGCAUGGUGCUCACCGUGAUAGGAAUUUCACUCUGCAUCACAAGCUCAGUUCCAUGGACUGCAGAACUCCAGCUGCAUGGAAAGGGCCAGCUGCAGACUUUGAGCCAGAAAUGCAAACGGGAGGCCUCUGGGACUCAGUCAGAGCGCUUUGGCUGAAUGAGGGGUGGAACCGAGGGAAGAAGGUGCGUCGGAGUGGCAGAUGCAGGAAAUGAGCUGUCUAUUAGCCUUGCCUGCCCCACCCAUGAGGUAGGCAGAAAUCCUCACUGCCAGCCCCUCUUAAACAGGUAGAGAGCUGUGAGCCCCAGCCCCACCUGACUCCAGCACACCUGGCGAGUAGUAGCUGUCAAUAAAUCUAUGGUAAACAGACAAGAGGUUAGUAAGUAUUCUUUUAUUGUGACAAACCCUCUCCCAGGCUUAGUCAGCUACUCCUUUCUCUGGCCAGAGAAUCCCAUAAGGAAAUAGCCCCCACAGCCAGGGCUGCUCUGCUCAGAGGAAGGGAAGGCUGGGCUGUGGGUUUAGGAGCAGGAGAACGGGGAGGGCUGAGGAGGCCGCAGUGUACCCUGUGAGCCCAGCGGAGGUGCUGGCUCCUGAGGAACAAGCUGCUGGAGGCUAAGGACAAAAGGUGGCCAGAGUAGUGGUCCCCAGUUGCCCUCUGGAGCUGCUGGCUCUCAAGAUGGCAGAGCUGGGGCUGAGGCUGAGAUAGCAGCCCCAGCCCCAGGCUGGUUUUCCAGGGACAAGGCCUCUUCCACUAUCUGUGCUGCCCUCUGCAGGAGGUGGAAGGCCAUACAGAAUGGAGCCGUGAGUAUGGCCAGCCUCCAGCUCUCAGCCAGGAGGUCCCCAACCCCAAGGAAGGAAGAAACUGGAAAUUAGGAACUGCUUCCUCAUUUAACAAGGUAGGAAGUUAGGAGAUCAUUUACUUUCAAUCACAAGGGAGGAGAACUGUUCCUGGGGCCCAAGGCUGCCAGUUUCCAGCUCAGAGCUCCUCCCACCCCAACAUACUGUUUCCUGAUCCAACAGCUUACCUGAUCCAAGGGCUCCUCUGUCUGAGUGUCUUCAUCAUCUGCUACUUCCAGGGCCCCCGCUGUCUCCUUCCUUCGGUGGGGAGCUCCAUAUACUCCUAUAACUCCUAAAGAGGGGAGGCAGCACUGGGUGAUGCCCAGGCUGAAGAGCCCUCAGCAUUCCUGCCCUGGACCUUCAUGCUAGCCCCUUUCCCUCCCCUGAACCUGGUUCUGCAUUCCCCACCACCUCCCAGGAUGGCAAGGAAGUGAGAGGUGGGCCUUUGGUCCCACCCCCAUCCCCUCUAUAUCCCACCCCUGAAGUCUUAUCGCUUUAAGCACUGCCCUUUCCAGGUGCUUCUUUUCAUGUGAUGAGGCCCUGUGAAGAAGGGACAGGAUAUACAGACGGGGGCAGCUGGAGACAGUUAUGAUGAGUGCCGGCUUUGUGUCUGAGCAUUCUGCUCCCAUGGACAUCCCCAACAACAGCAGGGACCAACCUAUGUCACUGUCAAAGGGCAGCUGAGAAGGGCCUGAGCCCCAGGGACCCCUCACCUGAUGGGAAUGAGAGUGUGGGGAGCUUGCUUCUUGGCUGAAUGGUCUGCUGGGGUCUGGCAUAGAAAGCAGAUGGCUUAAUUCGGUCUGGUUCCUUUGGAGAGGGCUGGGUUACCUGGGCCCUGUGGCCUUGGGCCUAGAGAAGGGACACUGGGCUUGGACCCUGAUUGCUGGCCAUUCUUACCUUUCCUACUCCCCAGUUCAGGCUUCAGAGAGCCCCUGACGCCUGCAGGAACAUGGCAGAGGAGACACCGUCUGUCUUCACAAAGUACGUCCUCCCUCCUUGCUGCCUCUUCCCACCAGCCUGACUUAUCCAGGGACAGAGCAGUAGAUGCCUGGCACUCCUCGAUGCCCAGUGAAACCAGACUGUGCUUCCCCACCCCCACCACCAUGCCCCAUGCUCACUGGCUCAUUUCUUGGGAGGGCUUAGAGCUGGAUAAUAUAAGUUCCCUUGGA